AUGCUCGCCGCCUCCAUCUUCCGUCCGACACUGCUGCUCUGCUGGCUGGCUGCUCCCUGGCCCACCCAGCCCGAGAGUCUCUUCCACAGCCGGGACCGCUCGGACCUGGAGCCGUCCCCACUGCGCCAGGCCAAGCCCAUUGCCGACCUCCACGCUGCUCAGCGGUUCCUGUCCAGAUACGGCUGGUCAGGGGUGUGGGCGGCCUGGGGGCCCAGUCCCGAGGGGCCGCCGGAGACCCCCAAGGGCGCCGCCCUGGCCGAGGCGGUGCGCAGGUUCCAGCGGGCGAACGCGCUGCCGGCCAGCGGGGAGCUGGACGCGGCCACCCUAGCGGCCAUGAACCGGCCGCGCUGCGGGGUCCCGGACAUGCGCCCACCGCCCCCCUCCGCCCCGCCUUCGCCCCCGGGCCCGCCCCCCAGAGCCCGCUCCAGGCGCUCCCCGCGGGCGCCGCUGUCCUUGUCCCGGCGGGGUUGGCAGCCCCGGGGCUACCCCGACGGCGGAGCUGCCCAGGCCUUCUCCAAGAGGACGCUGAGCUGGCGGCUGCUGGGCGAGGCCCUGAGCAGCCAACUGUCCGUGGCCGACCAGCGGCGCAUUGUGGCGCUGGCCUUCAGGAUGUGGAGCGAGGUGACGCCGCUGGACUUCCGCGAGGACCUGGCCGCCCCCGGGGCCGCGGUCGACAUCAAGCUGGGCUUUGGGAGAGGCCGGCACCUGGGCUGUCCGCGGGCCUUCGAUGGGAGCGGGCAGGAGUUUGCACACGCCUGGCGCCUAGGUGACAUUCACUUUGACGACGACGAGCACUUCACACCUCCCACCAGUGACACGGGCAUCAGCCUUCUCAAGGUGGCCGUCCAUGAAAUUGGCCAUGUCCUGGGCUUGCCUCACACCUACAGGACGGGAUCCAUAAUGCAACCAAAUUACAUUCCCCAGGAGCCUGCCUUUGAGUUGGACUGGUCAGACAGGAAAGCAAUUCAAAAGCUGUAUGGCUCCUGUGAGGGAUCAUUUGAUACUGCGUUUGACUGGAUUCGCAAAGAGAGAAACCAAUAUGGAGAGGUGAUGGUGAGAUUUAGCACAUAUUUCUUCCGUAACAGCUGGUACUGGCUUUAUGAAAAUCGAAACAAUAGGACACGCUAUGGGGACCCUAUCCAAAUCCUCACUGGCUGGCCUGGAAUCCCAACACACAACAUAGAUGCCUUUGUUCACAUCUGGACAUGGAAAAGAGAUGAACGUUAUUUUUUUCAAGGAAAUCAAUACUGGAGAUAUGACAGUGACAAGGAUCAGGCCCUCACAGAAGAUGAACAAGGAAAAAGCUAUCCCAAAUUGAUUUCAGAAGGAUUUCCUGGCAUCCCAAGUCCCCUAGACACGGCGUUUUAUGACCGAAGACAGAAGUUAAUUUACUUCUUCAAGGAGUCCCUUGUAUUUGCAUUUGAUGUCAACAGAAAUCGAGUACUUAAUUCUUAUCCAAAGAGGAUUACUGAAGUUUUUCCAGCAGUAAUACCACAAAAUCAUCCUUUCAGAAAUAUAGAUUCCGCUUAUUACUCCUAUGCAUACAACUCCAUUUUCUUUUUCAAAGGCAAUGCAUACUGGAAGGUAGUUAAUGACAAGGACAAACAACAGAAUUCCUGGCUUCCUGCUAAUGGCUUAUUUCCAAAAAAGUUUAUUUCAGAGAAGUGGUUUGAUGUUUGUGACGUCCAUAUCUCCACACUGAACAUGUAAUAAGAAAAAGUAGGAAAUGGAGGGUCAUAGGACUUCGCUAAAAUUCUGAUACUGUUUACAAAGAAAACCGGAUUUUCAGUAGCUGAAGAAAAUAUGGCACUGUAAGUUAAAACCCAAUGGGAAAAGCCUUAGUUGAACUUUUAAAAUACUUGAUUUAAAAACAAUUGCUCAGGCAAAACAUAAUUCAUAAACUAAAAGGUUUAAAAAAA